ACUCCGGCUCCAGCGGCCAGCGCGCGCGGGCCCAGGCCGCCCGGCUCCAGCCCAGCAGUAGCGGCAGCAGCGGCGGCGGCGGCAGUGCGCGCGAGGCCCUGCGCCCCCAGCAGCUCCUCCCUGGCGCCGUGCAUGGAGACGCGGCCCGCCACCCGCCGCUGAGCCCCCGCCGCCCGGCCGGGACCCGCCAGGGCUGGGGUGGCCUCGGGCUCCGGCCGGCCCCGCCGCCCGAGGGCUGCGCGCGGCCCGCGGGCCUCGCCGCCCCGCGCGGAUCGUCGCGGCCCGGCCGUCCCGUCCCAGGAAGUGGCCGUCCUGAGCGCCAUGGCUCACUCCCCGGUGCAGUCGGGCCUGCCCGGCAUGCAGAACCUAAAGGCAGACCCAGAAGAGCUUUUUACAAAACUAGAGAAAAUUGGGAAGGGCUCCUUUGGAGAGGUGUUCAAAGGCAUUGACAAUCGGACUCAGAAAGUGGUUGCCAUAAAGAUCAUUGAUCUGGAAGAAGCUGAAGAUGAGAUAGAGGACAUUCAACAAGAAAUCACAGUGCUGAGUCAGUGUGACAGUCCAUAUGUAACCAAAUAUUAUGGAUCCUAUCUGAAGGAUACAAAAUUAUGGAUAAUAAUGGAAUAUCUUGGUGGAGGCUCCGCACUAGAUCUAUUAGAACCUGGCCCAUUAGAUGAAACCCAGAUCGCUACUAUAUUAAGAGAAAUACUGAAAGGACUCGAUUAUCUCCAUUCGGAGAAGAAAAUCCACAGAGACAUUAAAGCGGCCAACGUCCUGCUGUCUGAGCAUGGCGAGGUGAAGCUGGCGGACUUUGGCGUGGCUGGCCAGCUGACAGACACCCAGAUCAAAAGGAACACCUUCGUGGGCACCCCAUUCUGGAUGGCACCCGAGGUCAUCAAACAGUCGGCCUAUGACUCGAAGGCAGACAUCUGGUCCCUGGGCAUAACAGCUAUUGAACUUGCAAGAGGGGAACCACCUCAUUCCGAGCUGCACCCCAUGAAAGUUUUAUUCCUCAUUCCAAAGAACAACCCACCGACGUUGGAAGGAAACUACAGUAAACCCCUCAAGGAGUUUGUGGAGGCCUGUUUGAAUAAGGAGCCGAGCUUUAGACCCACUGCUAAGGAGUUAUUGAAGCACAAGUUUAUACUACGCAAUGCAAAGAAAACUUCCUACUUGACCGAGCUCAUCGACAGGUACAAGAGAUGGAAGGCCGAGCAGAGCCAUGACGACUCGAGCUCCGAGGAUUCCGACGCGGAAACAGAUGGCCAAGCCUCGGGGGGCAGUGAUUCUGGGGACUGGAUCUUCACAAUCCGAGAAAAAGAUCCCAAGAAUCUCGAGAAUGGAGCUCUUCAGCCAUCGGACUUGGACAGAAAUAAGAUGAAAGACAUCCCGAAGAGGCCUUUCUCUCAGUGUUUAUCUACAAUUAUUUCUCCUCUGUUUGCAGAGUUGAAGGAGAAGAGCCAGGCGUGCGGAGGGAACUUGGGGUCCAUUGAAGAGCUGCGAGGGGCCAUCUACCUAGCGGAGGAGGCGUGCCCUGGCAUCUCCGACACCAUGGUGGCCCAGCUCGUGCAGCGGCUCCAGAGAUACUCUCUAAGUGGUGGAGGAACUUCAUCCCACUGAAAUUCCUUUGGCAUUUGGGGUUUUGUUUUUCCUUUUUUCCUUCUUCAUCCUCCUCCUUUUUUAAAAGUCAACGAGAGCCUUCGCUGACUCCACCGAAGAGGUGCGCCACUGGGAGCCACCCCAGCGCCAGGCGCCCGUCCAGGGACACACACAGUCUUCACUGUGCUGCAGCCAGAUGAAGUCUCUCAGAUGGGUGGGGAGGGUCAGCUCCUUCCAGCGAUCAUUUUAUUUUAUUUUAUUACUUUUGUUUUUAAUUUUAACCAUAGUGCACAUAUUCCAGGAAAGUGUCUUUAAAAACAAAAACAAACCCUGAAAUGUAUAUUUGGGAUUAUGAUAAGGCAACUAAAGACAUGAAACCUCAGGUAUCCUGCUUUAAGUUGAUAACUCCCUCUGGGAGCUGGAGAAUCGCUCUGGUGGAUGGGUGUACAGAUUUGUAUAUAAUGUCAUUUUUACGGAAACCCUUUCGGCGUGCAUAAGGAAUCACUGUGUACAAACUGGCCAAGUGCUUCUGUAGAUAACGUCAGUGGAGUAAAUAUUCGACAGGCCAUAACUUGAGUCUAUUGCCUUGCCUUUAUUACAUGUACAUUUUGAAUUCUGUGACCAGUGAUUUGGGUUUUAUUUUGUAUUUGCAGGGUUUGUCAUUAAUAAUUAAUGCCCCUCUCUUACAGAACACUCCUAUUUGUACCUCAACAAAUGCAAAUUUUCCCCGUUUGCCCUACGCCCCUUUUGGUACACCUAGAGGUUGAUUUCCUUUUUCAUCGAUGGUACUAUUUCUUAGUGUUUUAAAUUGGAACAUAUCUUGCCUCAUGAAGCUUUAAAUUAUAAUUUUCAGUUUCUCCCCAUGAAGCGCUCUCGUCUGACAUUUGUUUGGAAUCGUGCCACUGCUGGUCUGCGCCAGAUGUACCGUCCUUUCCAAUACGAUUUUCUGUUGCACCUUGUAGUGGAUUCUGCAUAUCAUCUUUCCCACCUAAAAAUGUCUGAAUGCUUACACAAAUAAAUUUUAUAACACGCUUAUUUUGCAUACUCCUUGAAAUGUGACUCUUCAGAGGACAGGGCACCUGCUGUGUAUGUGUGGCCGUGCGUGUGUACUCGUGGCUGUGUGUGUGUGAUGAGACACUUUGGAAGACUCCAGGGAGAAGUCCCCAGGCCUGGAGCUGCCGAGUGCCCAGGUCAGCGCCCUGGACUGCUUGCGCACUUGCUCACCGAGAUGAUGCAGUUGGAGGUUGCUGAUCUGUGCGAUUGCUGUAGCGGUUGCCGGGGACCUUAAGAGUUAUUUUGCUUCUCUGGAAGGGGCCUAUGCUUGCUAGGCAGGCAGCCAGUGUGUCUGUUUUUCUUGGUUUGCUGUGGGACCUUGCUUGGCGAGGGGGAAAAUCUCUGGGUUUCUGGAGUGGGAGGGUUCGUGCAGCAGCUGUUGACUGGUACAUGAAGCAUUCUUUUAUGUUUGUUGAAGCUGAUGAUUGACAUCUCCCGUGGGUGUGCCAGUUCUUGUGGAGUUAAGACAGGAUUUUUGGAAGCAAGGAAGUUAGUGGGUGAGCUUGGGGAUGUAGCUCAGCUAUCUGCUGGUCUAGUGGCCUCUAAGCUAUAGGGAGGGGACAGAGCCCUGAGCUACAGAUGCUUGAGUGGGUUAUUGUGUCGGUUUGCUAGUGCAGUCUGGUUUUUAAGCUCUAAAAUUGAGGUAUUUUAUUAGAAGUGGAUUUGGGUUGAACUCUUAAUUUGUAUAAGGGAUAUAUUUUGGUUGGGGAAAUAGAACUGAGUUGCUAAUUCUUAUUGUACUCAUUACUCCAUACAAGAAUGUUAUGUUGAAUAAUAAAAUUGGAGAAGAUUUCAUUUUGUGUUUCCAGGGAGUAUUCUGUGUGGGGAACUGUUUCCUUACGUGAGGCCGGCGGCAUAAGUCAAAGAUGAGUUUUGUCCUUGCGAAUCACACAGAUUGAGUCUGUGUUCCCCAGGGUGUGCCGUUACCUGAUUUUUAAGUGAGCCAGGGCGGACAGCAGCUUUUCUGAUUUACAGAGUUCUUCAGAUUUACAAAUGGACAAUGACAUCACAGUUUUUAGCACUGAAGCCAGUCUCAUGCUAGUAACAGUGGGUGAGCCGCUCGAGGGACUGGGUUCUAAUGAAUACUGGUAUGAACGGGGAGUCUCUGCAGUCGCCAGACAAAUCAUACUCAGCCCCUUCCCCCGUAGAGCAACAAGUGGUUCUUUUAGAGUUGACUGGCAGCAUUUCCUGUCGGGGGAGGUGGGGUUUGAUGGAGUUAGAAAGCUCGCCUCUGUGUACAUUCUCUCCUGGGCUGUUACUUUCUGUAGACGCACAAAAUCAGCCCCAAUGUUUUUAAGGGCAUCUUAGCCAAGGAAGCUGGCUUUUGUGUCGCCACUUCCAGGCCUGCAUUAAGAGAGAGCCCAGGCACCAGGGCUACCACUGGAACCUGCCUCAGCGUCAACUGCUGCUGGUCUGUAGCCAGGCCCAGCCUUUGAGACGGGUUUACUGUCACCAGUAGCCUCUCAGUGCCAGCCCUGAGCUGCUCCUGGCUCAGCUGCCCAGAGCCUGCAGCCUGGGGAGGUACUCAGCCUCUGGGAGACGAGGGCCGUGGACUGGGUGGCUGGUAGCUCCUGCGUUUUUGAGCUGUGUCCUGGCUGGCUGCUGCCAAUGAGGUGGACACCAGUGUGGUUUGGGGUGCACUGGCCACUUCUUGCUGGGUUCUGAUUUUCUUGGAAGUGCAUCUGCCUUCCUUAUCCAAUAGUUUUAUCCCUGCAUUGCUCUUGUGAAGUGGCUGGUUUGGUUCUGUAUGUAGCAUUUUGUACCUUUCCUCUGGCAAAACACUGUCAGUUUAUAAACAUUUUUUAUAUUUCCCUCCUUUAAAAACAGCUUGUGUAUUUCUGCUAUAAAAUGUGUCAGCAAAGGCAGAGUGACCUAAUAGGGCAUGUUCUUAAGCACAGGGACUGUAUCAUGCAGGGGCCAAUAAAGCUCAAGAAAACGAGUAUCUGCAUCAUUGUGUGUCUCAUGUGUAGUGUGUCUCAAACUCCACUCAGAUGGACUGUUACCCACACUAGUAUUUUCUUGAGGGCACACAGGAAGCAGAGGUGCUGGUCACAGGUCAGAACCACCAGUGUCCAGCAAGUAGUUUGGAAUCAAUCAAUCAUUCAGAAAUAAAUAGCUGAGGAGACUGCCUUGUCCCCAAGUCUCCAGGAAUGAGUGAGUGGUGACUUCUGGAGGGAGCCUGAUGCUGCUGUGUGGCCCGGAGCUGUUUGUUUGCUCUGCCCCUGCCUGGAGGUGGGGGGAGCAUAGGGAACAGUGGGGGGCAGGCCCUCCCUGUGUCACUCUGAACACUGGGGCUUUAGAAACCCUUGCUGGAGUGUCCCCUUCCCCCCUCCCCCCCCACACAGAAAAUGAAGACUACAGACAAAGUUGGUUGUUUUGCCUUAAAACAUCAAUAUGCUGGAUUGUGGCGUGAGGUAUUUUUAUUCCCUUUGUUAGUACUGGAAACCGUCUGGUACAUCUUGUAAGGCAAAUGAUUAACACACGGCAGGCUCUUCGUCCGUUUGCAAGUUGCUGUUUGUUUCCAGCUACACCAGUCAGAGCUCCACAGAGAGGGUGCGUUCCUGGUUCUCAGGUGGGCAGGUGCUAUGGUGCGGGGCGCUGGAAAGAAUGGGGUUGAAUUGGCCCUCGCCUCCGCUUGUUUGAGACUCUCGUUAGAAAGGGCUUAGGAAAACCAAGGGAAUGGCAGCCACCCCAUCACCAUCGAGAACAGGCAGACGUUUCCCGAGUAGGGGCCAAAGCCACUGGAAACCGUGUUCCCUGUGCAGUCCGACUGACACUACCCCAUGCCUGGGGGGAAUGAGUAUAAAAAGGGAAAUGUUUUUGAAGACAGGCACGAUAUAUACUACUAGAGAAUGCGCAGUUUCAAACCACAGUUGCAGGAGGAUAUAGGAAUAACGACAGGUGCCGGGGACUACGUACCAUGAUUUCAUAGUGCUCUGCAGCCAGCAGGCUCACUAAACGCUCAUCACGGAACAUACCACAAAUGGUGCUGAUCAAUGACACACGGGUUUUCAUGCUUGUGACACAGACAGACAGCAAAACACCACGGCUUAUUAUCUUCCCAUUGUGUACACCACUCACAGGACGGUGACAGUCCAGGUAUUGCACUGGAUCUCGGCUUUGCUUAACAGAAAACAACCCUGCUACGGUUGGAAAGAGUUACCACUUAAAACGAUUUGGUCAACUUGCACCAAGAAGUAGGUUGGGAACAGGUGUUUUCAGGUGAGCGUGAAACCCCGCAGUGGAACGCUGUGUGCUGCAAAUUGCUUAUUAAUCAGAGAAGUGAGUCCUACUAACUUCCUAUUAUUACAAAAGUAGAAAGACUGAAAAAAAAAAUGAAAUCUGAAAAUGAUCUCAUUUGCUUAAGGCUGCACUGAGUGUAUUGCAAACAAACAAACAAACACCGGGAAGUCCACUUCGUAAAAUGCAGCAGCCAAUAGGUGAAAAUAAUAAAAGAAAGAACUUUUUUUAGGAAGAAAAACACUUGCCCUGUCUUGUGUUGAACGGAUGUGUGUGUACUGUUUUUCAGGGGCAGGGUGGAGGGAAGAUGUCAUUUGGCACUCUCGUAAUGACAAUGUUUUAAUACUGGCACUAGCUAAAGAACAGCGCCCCCAGCGGAUGCCAGGACUGGAGGUGGGAGCGCUGUUCAUUCAGACGCUGAGAGGUCGGGGUUAAAAAACGCGGCUGUGGAGACAGGAGAGCUGCUGGGAAGCCAUGUUUUUGAUUUUCAGACAGGUGUUAAUUUUACCAGGCUUCAUUAAUACAGAAGAAAGGAAACGUCUUCCAGGAAAGCAGCCACUGCGGAAACGAGUGUGUCCGGCCAUCAAUACACAAGAGACUCUUUGUGACUCAACACGUGGGGUCGCGAGGCAGAGCUGGUGGCACUGCGGAUCACUUCCAUCCACCUGCAACACGGGAACGCCAGUUAGUCAACCUUUUGUUUGGACGGACUCCUGACACUUUGGUGGGCAUCGCUUACAGAAACACAAGGUGAAGUCAGGCCGCCUGGUUGGUAAUCUGCCACUUCAGCAGAAGAGCAAGGGAACAGCCAGCACCCAGGCGUUCCUGAGGUACAGUGGAGACCCACUGGCCUGGGCACUCACUCAGUGUGGAGCUGGAAGUACCUUGCUGCAGUGACACUGCCCGCUCCAUUGGAGCAGUUAGGAGCGAGGUGGCCUCUGGUUGCUGGGGAGAACGCUACCUCCUAUUUUCAUGGACAUGGCAGAGAAUGGCGGGACGUGUCCCAUCCUGCUUAGUGGAAGCUCUCCCUUCCUUUUUUCUUUUUCUUUUUUUUUUGAGACAGGGUCUGGCUCUGUCACUCAUACUGGAGUUCAGUGGUGCAGUUAUCGCCCACUGUAGCUACCUCCUGGGCUCAAUCGAUCCUCCAGCCUUGGCCUCCCAGGAGAUGGGACUACAGGCUUGCACCACCACGCCCAAAUCUCCCUUUUUAUAUAUUUGUGUAUUUGCUCUCUACCGGUGCUUCUCAAAUGGGUGCAAUGCUGUCCCAUUUGGUAAAGUCUGGAGACAUUUUUAGAUGUCCCAACUGAGGGGUUGCUGCGGGCAUCUAGUGGGUGGCCAGGGAUGCCGCUGAACAUCCUGCACAAUGCAGGACGGACUCCCCAAAUUACCUGGCCUUGUCCCAGGCCUUUCAGGAUCUGGACUGCAAGGCUGGACCCUUUGUCACAAUAAUAGCAAAAUCCCAACUUUGAUCAACCCAGCUCUCAACCCAGCUCUCGAGCUCAGUCCAGGAUCAGAUUUGAGAAUGGCUCUCCUCUAGGUUCCUUUUUCAGGUGAUGUUGUUUAGGAGGUGCUCAGCAUAUUGCUGAGGACCCCUCCCCUUCUGCCUCCCGGGGCGAGGAGGGCUCAGCAGGGCAAACUGCACAAGUAGUCGGCUUGGGGAUGCAAUUUGCAGAGGCCCAGGAUCUCUAUUCAAAAUAUGAAUUGCAGGAACAGUCUUAGGCCUGACUGUUGCAUUUCUUUCUUGGCUAAAUGAAGUCUGCAGUCCCUGCCAUUACACCAUGUAGGCAGUCUCACUGGGGCUUAGCUUCAUCAUCCCGGACACGUUAUGUCAGAGAUCUCCAAGCAAGAUGUCUAGGGCCUCAGCCAACACCGUGCAGGGUAAGGGCGCAGGGAAGUUGGGACCCCACUUUCUGCCAUGAGAACAGAAUCGCCUGCUGGUGUCGGGCAGUGGGACCCCAGGUCUAAACGCUUAGUUGGCAGGGAAGGGUGGGGCCAUCUCACUCGCUGACUUGGGAGAAAUCCUGAUGUUUGGAAGAGGGGGUCCUCUUCUGCAGGGCCCUGUGCGUGGGAAGGGGGUGUCUACCUUUCGAACGUGUACUCGCUUUCCGCCCUGAAGUAGUAGACGUGGGACUUGAAGUGCAGCUUGAACACGUAGUCUUUCUGGAUGUUCUCGGACUCAGAGGGGAUGGUGAGCGAGUAGCCGAGCAGAGGCAGGCUGGCAAGGGGAUGAUUGUCCUGGAAAGGGGAAACAAAGCAAAGUGGCUUUUCGGGGUCAGCUUCUGCUGCUGGGCCUGGCUGCUGCCCCGCAUCAGACAGGGACUUGGGAGCCCAGGCAGCUCCCUCCUCGGGCGUGGGCCUGGAAGGGACCAUGGCAGCCAGUGUUUGCCUGUACGUGAUGGCCCGGGUGGCAAGUCCCGCCAGGACUGAGCUGUAGAUAAAGCCAACCCCCGUCCCUUGUCCAGGCAGAAGACAGGUGGCCCUUCCUAGGGCAGAAGUUGUCCUUCAGUGGAUGAUAAUGUCAGUCUUCCCUAGAGUUGAGGGCCUCGGGUGGACAGGGCCCCCCGCCAGCAUCCCUGUCAUCCCCGUGACACCUGGAGCCCAAGAGGCCUGAGUCAUUCCAGAGGAGGGCGGCCCCCUCACCUCAUGCUGCCACCCCCAAGGUCCCAGGGCCACCUGCCCUGUGCGAGACACUUACCUGGUGUGAUUUGUAGAAGAACAGGCAGAAGUUUGUGAACACCACCCACAGCUUCUGCCACCCGUUGCUGUUUUUGAAUUUCCUCAGCAGGUUUCCAGACAACUGAUUCUGAAAGGCAAGGAGGCCUGUGAGAAGCACAGCGGGCACCUGCCCCAGGAGGGCACAGAGAGCAGCUCUCCCUGCACCAGGGCCCUGGGCUGGGGCAUGUCCGUGACUGAAGGAUGUGGGCCCCACCCCCGCUCCCCCGUGUGUGGGGAGACUUGGCAGGUCCUGGGACCCUGAUCUCAUCACUUCCCCUUGUCACUUGCUGUGGGGCAUCUUGGGGUCCCUGUGUCCCCCCAAAAGACACGUUGAGGUCCUGACUACCAGUACCUUAGAACACAGGCUUAUUUGGAAAUAGGCUCGUUGCAGGGUAACUAGUGAAGACGAGAUCACACUGGGGUAGGGUGGGCCCUAAAUCCAACGGGAGUGGUGUCCUGAGGAGAAGAGCCACCUUGAGGGGAGAGGGGUGUGCCCUGUGACACCGAGGCAGAAAUGGGGGCGCAGGACCCCAUGCAUUGCCAGCAGGCGGAAGCUGAAGGAGGGAAAGAUCCAUCCCAACAAGCUCAGAGCAGCACUCGUUUUGAGGGGCCAGGCACCCUACCCAGGAAGUGGGGCCUGGGGUGCAUGUGAGUGGCUCCCACAUGCCCUCUAGUGGCCCAGGAGGCAGUUGCAGCCCUGCCCACCUCCAGGCUCAGGGCCGGCCCAGCCCCUGGAGCAUUGUUAGGAUGCGCUGCAGCCCAGCUAGGGGGCAGGGACAGGCACCUGUGUCCAUGCUACCUCCAAACAACUCUGAGCAGGCCUGACGCACUGGUGGCUCAUUUCGUCCCUUUGCCAAAGUGACAUCACCAGCAGAGACUCAAAGCAGUUGCACCACCUUGUAAAGGCACUUAAUGCCACUGAAUUGUUCCCGUAAAAAUCGUUAAGUUGGCCAAUAUUGUGGUAUAGCUAUUUUACCACAAUAAAAAAUACAGACCUCCGA